GGUGUUGGAGAGAGGGGUGAUGCCUGGUGCUGGUGGAACCCCUGCACAGAGACGGACACAGGAUGAGCUCUAAGUACCCGCGGUCUGUCCGGCGCUGCCUGCCCCUCUGGGCCCUAACACUGGAAGCAGCUCUCAUUCUCCUCUUCUAUUUUUUUACCCACUAUGACGCUUCCUUAGAGGAUCAAAAGGGGCUCGUGGCAUCCUAUCAAGUUGGCCAAGAUCUGACCGUGAUGGCGGCCAUUGGCUUGGGCUUCCUCACCUCGAGUUUCCGGAGACACAGCUGGAGCAGUGUGGCCUUCAACCUCUUCAUGCUGGCGCUUGGUGUGCAGUGGGCAAUCCUGCUGGACGGCUUCCUGAGCCAGUUCCCUUCUGGGAAGGUGGUCAUCACACUGUUCAGUAUUCGGCUGGCCACCAUGAGUGCUUUGUCGGUGCUGAUCUCAGUGGAUGCUGUCUUGGGGAAGGUCAACUUGGCGCAGUUGGUGGUGAUGGUGCUGGUGGAGGUGACAGCUUUAGGCAACCUGAGGAUGGUCAUCAGUAAUAUCUUCAACACAGACUACCACAUGAACAUGAUGCACAUCUACGUGUUCGCAGCCUAUUUUGGGCUGUCUGUGGCCUGGUGCCUGCCAAAGCCUCUACCCGAGGGAACGGAGGAUAAAGAUCAGACAGCAACGAUACCCAGUUUGUCUGCCAUGCUGGGCGCCCUCUUCUUGUGGAUGUUCUGGCCAAGUUUCAACUCUGCUCUGCUGAGAAGUCCAAUCGAAAGGAAGAAUGCCGUGUUCAACACCUACUAUGCUGUAGCAGUCAGCGUGGUGACAGCCAUCUCAGGGUCAUCCUUGGCUCACCCCCAAGGGAAGAUCAGCAAGACUUAUGUGCACAGUGCGGUGUUGGCAGGAGGCGUGGCUGUGGGUACCUCGUGUCACCUGAUCCCUUCUCCGUGGCUUGCCAUGGUGCUGGGUCUUGUGGCUGGGCUGAUCUCCGUCGGGGGAGCCAAGUACCUGCCGGGGUGUUGUAACCGAGUGCUGGGGAUUCCCCACAGCUCCAUCAUGGGCUACAACUUCAGCUUGCUGGGUCUGCUUGGAGAGAUCAUCUACAUUGUGCUGCUGGUGCUUGAUACCGUCGGAGCCGGCAAUGGCAUGUCACUCGGCUGGAACCUGGCUGUAAAAAUGGCUGAAGCAGGUGAUGAGGAGCUGAUGCGUUUGGACGUGUCUCAGAGAAAUCAUGGAGGCGCUGCGGUUCCUACCGGUUCUUGGAUGCCUUCUACAGAGACAACCAUAGCCCCAAAUUAUAGGGAUCACAUAUCAGUGGGAUUGGCUUCCAGGUCCUCCUCAGCAUUGGGGAACUCAGCUUGGCCAUCGUGAUAGCUCUCAUGUCUGGUCUCCUGACAGUUUCCUCAUUUGGCUGUUGGAUUUUAAGCAAAAGCAUCCAAGAAAAACAAGGCCUGUUCAAAAACAAGACAACUUCCUCUCACUGUUGCCUGCAUUUGUACGUGAGAAACGCUCAUGACAGCAAAGUCUCCAAUGUUCGCGCAGGCACUGGAGUCAGAGAAAAUGGAGUUGAAUCCUUUCUCUGCCACUCUUUGAGGAGAAUCUCACCAUUUAUUAUGCACUGUAGAAUACAACAAUAAAAUACAGCCAUGUACCACAUAACAACAUCUUGGUAAACAACAGACUGCAUAUAUGAUGGUGGUCAUCCAGUAAGCUAAGGUUAAUUUAUUAUUAUUCCUUGUUUUUUUUUUUUUUUUUUUUUUUUUGAGAUGUAGUCUUACUCUGUCACCCAGGCUAGAGUGCAAUGGCACCAUCUUGGCUCACUGCAACCUCUACCUCCUGGGUUCAAGCAAAUCUCCUGCCUCAGCCUCCAAAGUAGCUGGGAUUACAGGCACCCACCACAUCUGGCUAAUUUUUUGUAUUUUUAGUAAAGAUGGGGUUUCACCAUGUUGGCCAGGCUGAUCUCAAACUCCUGACCUCAAGUGAUCUGCCCGCCUCGGCCUCCCAAAGUGCUGGAACCACAGGCCUGAGCCACUGUGCCCAGCCUUGUUUGCUUUUUUAACAGAUAACAGUGUGCUCAUAGAAACUGCUUUGACAUGACUGCAAUCAUGUGCUUCAUAGAAACUUAAUUAGAUUAUACCACUAGAGUCUUCAGAUUUUUAUACUUUUUUUUUUUGAAACGGAGUCUCACUCUGUCACCAGGCUGGAGUGCAGUGCCGCAAUCUCGGCUCACUGCAACCUCCGCCUCCCAGGUUCAAGCAAUUCUCCUGCCUCAGCCUCCCGAGUAGCUGGAAUUACAAGUGCGCACUACCACACCCAGCUAAUUUUUGCAUUUUUACUUGACAGGGUUUCACCAUGUUGGCUAGGAUAGUUUCACCAGGAUCUCUUGGCCUCAUGAUCAGCCUGCCUCGGCCUCCCAAAGUGCUGGGAUUACAGGUGUGAGCCACCGUGCCCAGCCUAUACUUCCCUUUUUGAAUACCAUUUGGUGUUUUGAAGAAUUAACAGCUUUGUGAACGUGGCAGUGCUUGUGAUUCAGGCUUCCAUUGAGACCAAGGGGAGAACCUGGUUGCAGGACAAACAGACGGACAGCGUGUGGCAGUGUUUAAAUGCUCUUCUGAAGGCUGAUACGACAGCUCUCUGUGCACUGAUUGCAUAUGCAUCCCAAGAUUAUAUUAUUGUUUUCUACUGCUAUGUGUCACACUUUGCCAAACAGGAUGUGGAAAAUGAAUAAGCGGUUUUCUUAGGCACUUCUUAACAGACAAUUGGUCAAAAUGAACUCCAUUGCUUAAGAAACACAUAAACACCAUUUAGUCACUGAACAUAGCUAUAUGUAUGGUUGUUACUAUGGGAAAUCUUGUUUUGCCAAUUUUCUUUGAAAAUUCUGGCAGACCAAGGUUCUUUUUGUUUACAUAAUACUUGAAAAAUAAAAAUGAACAAGCUAACAAACUA